AGUCCGCCCGAGCUGUGGUUGUGGGCGCCGGACAAGUCCAAGGCGCCUCCUCCCAAUAUGGACAGCCGCUACAACAGCACUGCGGGCAUCGGGGACUUGAACCAGCUGAGCGCUGCCAUCCCGGCCACGCGGGUGGAGGUGUCCGUGUCCUGCAGAAAUCUUCUUGACAGAGACACAUUUUCUAAAUCUGAUCCAAUUUGUGUCUUAUAUGUACAAGGAGUUGGAAAUAAAGAAUGGAGAGAGUUUGGAAGAACUGAAGUAAUUGAUAAUACUUUAAAUCCUGAUUUUGUAAGAAAGUUUAUUCUGGACUACUUUUUUGAAGAAAGAGAGAAUCUUCGUUUUGACUUGUAUGAUGUUGAUUCAAAGAGCCCCAACUUAUCCAAACAUGACUUUCUGGGACAAGUGUUUUGUACAUUGGGAGAGAUCGUUGGUUCACAGGGAAGUCGCCUGGAAAAACCAAUAGUAGGAAUUCCAGGGAAGAAAUGUGGUACAAUCAUACUUACAGCAGAGGAAUUAAACUGUUGCAGGGAUGCCGUUUUGAUGCAAUUUUGUGCGAACAAAUUGGACAAGAAGGACUUCUUUGGAAAAUCAGAUCCUUUCCUUGUAUUUUAUCGAAGUAAUGAAGAUGGCAGUUUUACAAUUUGUCACAAGACAGAAGUUGUCAAAAACACUCUAAAUCCAGUAUGGCAAGCAUUCAAGAUCUCAGUCAGAGCAUUAUGUAAUGGAGACUAUGACAGAACAAUCAAAGUAGAGGUGUAUGACUGGGACCGAGAUGGAAGUCAUGAUUUCAUUGGAGAAUUUACAACAAGCUAUAGGGAACUUUCUAGAGGGCAGUCACAAUUCAACGUAUAUGAGGUGGUGAAUCCCAAAAAGAAAGGAAAAAAGAAAAAAUAUACUAAUUCUGGAACAGUAACUUUACUCUCUUUCUUGGUAGAAACAGAAGUUUCAUUCCUUGACUACAUUAAGGGAGGGACGCAAAUCAAUUUCACAGUGGCUAUUGAUUUUACAGCAUCAAACGGCAACCCUGCUCAGCCCACUUCCCUCCACUACAUGAAUCCUUACCAACUGAAUGCCUAUGGUAUGGCACUAAAAGCAGUGGGAGAAAUUGUUCAAGAUUAUGACAGUGAUAAAAUGUUUCCAGCUCUAGGAUUUGGUGCAAAACUGCCUCCAGAUGGAAGGAUAUCUCACGAAUUUGCUUUGAAACUGCCAAUCUCAUUACCAACGGUGAGAAAAGUGCACCCAGGAGUUGUAUAACUCAACUCAGAGGCUCAGAAGUUAACCAUUGUCCCAAAGGACAGGACUUGAACCCAGGUCAGUCUUAUUUUAGAAUUCAUGCUCUUAACUACAGCUAAACCCCAUCUUAUAAAAGCACCUGUAAUCUCACCUCUUGGAUGCAUGCUUAUAUUAACACCAUGAUAUAUGUACCUUUAUAUAAGUUUUUAUAUAAAAUUUCAUCUUUCUCAAAUGUUUUAAGAGGAGUAUUACAUUUUUAUUUUUGUAUUUAUUCUUACUUUUCUAUUCCAUCACCCACACAAUUUCUAGAGAGGUUGCUGGAGGGCUUAAUUCUUUCUUCCAUGAAAUAGCCCACAUGCCACACUCCCAGUGUCAUAAAAAUGAGUAUCUGUUGGGAUUUUGUUGUGUCUUAGAAAAUUAAAAUCUCCCAGAAACUUAUAAAACCAUGAAAAUCACUCAUGUGAUUCUAAGUCUGAAGUGCCUCAGGAAAAAGGUCAUGAGCUAUUUUAAAGCCUAAGAAAAGGAAUAAUUGUGUUAAGCUAAAUGAGAGGUUUAUUAAUUUUCUCUCCAUACAUUUCUUCCUCCACUAGUGUGUAUUUUUUUCCUUUUUCCUCCCCUCCACUUUUCUCCUUUUCUGCUUUUCCUACCUCCACAUUUACCCCUUGUAACCAAAGCUAUACAAGUAUCUACUGCUAAGGAAUGAUAUAUAUUUUUGGUUAUUUACACCAUAGUCUGUUCUUUGAGCCCAAUUCGAACAUUUAUGGAAUAGAGAUCAUACCCCUUUAAAUCUAUGAAGAAUAGCCUCUCAAAUUGACGAUGAAAACAACAAUGAUUAUGUUGAUGAUAAUGCCUCAACUUUAAUAUUACCGAAUGAUUAUAUUACUUUAAUUUUUUUCAAAGCACUUCUGUUUUGUUGGAUAAAUAAGGCAGAUAUGGGUUAAGUAGGUCUUUAGUGAGAUAGUAUUUGAUUUCAUUCUUGCUGAAGUAUUCUGUGUUAAGCUCAUCCUAAGUCACUGCAAUAUCUAUCUGUAGGUACUGAAAAUGACAAAUACAAAAAGUUCAGUUUCAUGACAGUCUUGUCUUUCAUGAACUACCUGAUGUUAAUAAACCCUCGUAUUUCCAUGGUAUGAAUUUGUGAUAUAUGUUCUCUAACAUUAACCUAUUUAUCUCACCACAUUCACAUAAUUCUUUUGGAUAGCAAGGGAGUCUUCUUAACAACUUAAAUUACCCCCAGUGUAUAAGUUUUGGCCAGUACAGAUGUUGAACUUAAGCUUUGCUCGUUUGAAAAGGUCUCAGUAAAUCCCAGCUUUUUAUGUGAGACACACUAUGAGAAAAGGAAAAGGAAUGGGAGAGGAAAGGAAGAAUUUCCUAAUAUUACCAUUUCAAGACUUAUGGUUAUGAAAAGAAUGAGUCAUUGCUCUCCUCUCAUUAUCAUUCUUGAUGACUCCUUUUGGAUUUAUAACUGAAAACGCAAUAGUGCGGAGCUCUGGUAGAGGUAUUUCUAAUGAGCUUGUGGCCAGUGGUCCUUAAAAGAAGGUCUUCCAUGCGGACCAAUAGAGAAACGCUACACCUGUCCAAGUGAUUUCUCCUGGGAAAUACCUAAAUGCACUUGCAUGCUUUUCACUUAUUUUGGCAUUUAUACAAAUGUAUGCAAUUUAAUAUUUAUGUGUAUGUAUUUUUUUGCCAAGUAGGCACCAGUAAUUUAAUAACUAAGAGUCUUUAACACUGUACUGUAUAUAAAACAGAAGCUCAAUAGGUGUUUGUUCAUUGAAUAAAAGGAAGAAUUCUCUCAGCUUUUUCCCACAGUAAGCAACAGUCACAUUUCAGAGUAGAGCAACAGCCCCUAAGAGCUUCUUUUCAGUAUUUUGUCAGCUUGUUAGCCCUGCUGAAAACUGUCACAGGCUGCAGGCAGCAACAGAGAUGACAGACUUCUUGCAUGGAGAUGAAUCCACACCCUCAGCACAAUCCCUGAGGGAGCUAAACGGGAGGAAAAAUGGGUAAGAGCUGGGCACUCCUCCCCACUUAAGUCUGAGUGGUGAGAUUAUUAAUCAUUUUAAAGUCAGAUCUUUAUGCUUUUCUAUGUGUUCUACAAGUUAACAUGUGUUAUUUUAUAAAUGGAAAGGUUGUUAAUUAGGAGGGAAAUAUGAAAUAAGGCAUCCAUUGCCCUCUUCAUUAAUAAACAACAAAAUUAAAUGUGCUUAUUUUUUAAAAAAUCCUGUGUUUUACUUUUGUGUCAGAACCACAACUGGACUUAUUCUAAUUUGUUUUAACAAGCAAUAACUGAUUCCCUGCAUAAUUAUUUCAAGAAAUGAGUUUUUAAACACAUUUAAAAUGUUUUUACUUAUUUCACUAGUUUUGGGGGAACAGGUGUUUUUUGAUUACAUGGAUAAGUUCUUUAGUGGUGAUUUCUGAGAUUCUGAUGCACCCAUCACCUGAGCAGUGGUCACUGAGUUAUCCUUCACCUUCCUCCCACCUUUCCCCGCCAGUCUCCAAGUCCAUUAUAUCAUUCUUAUGCCUUUGCAUCUUCAUAGCUUAGCUCCCACUUAUAAGUGAGAACAGACAAUAUUUGGUUUUCUAUUCCUGAGUUACUUCACUUAGAAUAAUGGUCUCCAACUCCAUCUAGGUUGCCGUGAAUGCCAUUAUUCCAUUCCUUUUUAUGGUUGAGUAGAAUUGUAGUAUACACACACACACACACACACACACCACAUUUUCUUUAUCCACUUAUUGGUUGAUGGGCAUUUAGACUGGUUCCAUAUUUUUGCAAUUGCAAAUUGUGCCACUAUAAAGGUGUGUGCAAGUAACAGACUUAAAAAUCUUUUUAUAACUCAUUACAACUUUCUUAUUAAGAAGAAAAUCUCAUUUUAGUAGCUAUAAAAUAUUUUAAAUAAUCCUGAUAUAAUCCAGAGCAUAUACUAAAAAGAAGGCAUAAUUUUAUAUAAGGUAUUCUUAUCGUCUAAGACAUAUGAGGAAACCUUAGAGCAACUUAUUAUGGUAGGACUAAUUCAUAAAUCAUUAAACAUUCCAUGUUGAUGAAUAGAACAUCUAAUGAUUACCUUUCCAUUCUCAAAGAAGAGAAAAAUGGUGACCUUGUAGUUUCAAUUCCAGAGAAAUAGUGAUAACAUACAGUUUCAUCAAAACGUAAACCUCCAAUCAACAUGUUAAAAAAUAAAAGUAGCUCAGGACUACCCUAGUUUGUAACUGUUCCCUUAAGGUAGAUAUAUAAUACAUUUUUAUAUGCCCAAAAUCAGUAAUGAGUUUUAAUUUUAAUUAGCUUCAUACCUUAUCAAGGGAAAAGAGCACCAUAAAACCUUAAAGGAAUGUUAAAUAGGUCGGCUCAGAUUAACAUCAAAACACUAACUGCUUUGUGCUAAAUAUUAAACUUAUCUUUUACAUUCUGUUUUCAGCCAAGUCAUGCAACCAGUUUUAUAAUGUAAAGCAGGCUUUUAUUUUUAUACUUUCAAAAAUGUAUGAGGGUUAAUAAAAAUGUUUGAAGAAAAGACAAAA